CAAAGUGUUGGGAUUACAGGCAUCAGCCACCGCGCCUGGCCAAAAGGUAUACACUUCUAUCCACAGACUCCUUAGCAUUAAGAACUCCUGCGAAGACACUCUGGCUUUCGGAUUAGGCACUUCUAUAAAGUCCCCAUCCUUAGAAGUUGCCCACUGCCCUCCAAAUCCUGUACACCUUGUCUGUAUUGAAAUCUGAAGAUGCACCCUGAAUGCAGAAUGGGUCCAAAUCUCUAGCUUCAGACUACGAUUUUAGACAAAGACCUACCUUUGGGUGAUUUAGAUGCCCUAAAAUGUAGAGAAGUGUAAAACAUCAACAUCACCACCCCCAUUUACUUAUUUCAGAAGGAUGUGGGCAGAGUGGAAAGUGCUUCAGAGACUGUAUGUGCUGAUCAAGUCCUCAUCACCUUCCCAAAAAAUCCUCCUAAGACCCAAGAGCGGGUAAUCCUGGGUGAUUGGCUCAUUGUAGGAGGUCCUUGGUGUCACACAUGCUUGCAAGAUGGCUGGUGUGUGUCCUCAUGGGGCUGGAUCUGUUCCCCCCGUGUCUGCACCUUCAGACACAUAUAGUUUAGCUUUGGAGGCAGGGAGGGGCACUGCAAAUGUGAUUCGGCACUGAAACUAAUGGAUGUAUUUGGGGUUUAGGUUUGCAAAUGAAAUUCAAAAAAUCGGCAGUGACUCUUCUUGGACCAGGUGGAGAGCAGGAAGAAGGCCGGCAGCAGGUGUGGCUCGGGCAGAUUGGAGAGGCACAAUGGGGCACGUUUGCUAGACAAGCUUAUAACCCACACCAUGGAUAACUUAUUGGACUUUGCCUGAAAGGAGUCAUUAGUGACAUUGGAUAUUUGACCGUCUUGGCCACAGGUUUUUCAGAAUGAAUGGAAGAUCAUGCAGCAUGAGUCUCCACCGGACAUCGGGAACCCCACAGGGGCCUAGGAUGGUCAGUGGUCAUCACAUUCCUGCCAUCCGAGCCCACUCCGGGACUCCUGGCCCCUCGCCCUGUGGCAGCACAUCGAGUCCCACUAUGGCAAGCCUUGCUAACAACCUCCAUCUCAAGAUGCCCUCAGGAGGAGGGAUGGCUCCUCAGAACAACGUGGCUGAGAGCCGCAUCCAUCUGCCUGCCUUAAGCCCCAGGAGACAAAUGCUCACCAAUGGGAAGCCGCGAUUCCAGGUCACCCAGGCUGGAGGCAUGUCAGGGUCACAUACUUUAAAGCCAAAGCAGCAGGAGUUUGGAAGCCCUUUUCCUCCAAAUCCUGGGAAAGGGGCUCUUGGCUUUGGGCCUCAGUGCAAGUCCAUUGGAAAAGGCAGCUGCAACAAUCUAGUGGUCACCAGCAGUCCCAUGAUGGUUCAGCGACUGGGACUCAUUUCACCUCCAGCAAGCCAGGUCUCUACAGCAUGCAACCAGAUCAGUCCUAGCUUACAGAGGGCAAUGAAUGCAGCCAACCUGAAUAUACCUCCUUCAGAUACCAGGUCCCUUAUUUCGCGUGAGUCUUUGGCGUCCACGACCUUGAGUCUGACGGAAAGUCAGUCGGCCUCAAGCAUGAAGCAGGAGUGGUCCCAGGGCUACAGGGCCCUCCCUUCGCUCUCCAACCACGGCUCUCAGAAUGGCCUUGAUCUAGGGGAUCUCCUUAGCCUUCCUCCCGGGACAUCCAUGUCCAGCAAUAGUGUCUCUAACUCAUUACCAUCCUACCUUUUUGGCACGGAAAGUAGCCACUCUCCUUACCCUAGUCCUCGGCACUCAUCCACCAGGUCCCACUCGGCCCGCUCCAAGAAGAGAGCGCUGUCCUUGUCCCCGCUGUCCGAUGGCAUCGGGAUAGAUUUCAAUACCAUCAUCCGCACGUCGCCCACGUCCUUGGUGGCCUACAUCAACGGGUCGAGGGCUUCGCCGGCCAACCUGUCCCCGCAGCCGGAGGUCUACGGGCAUUUCCUGGGCGUGCGCGGCAGCUGCAUUCCCCAGCCGCGCCCGGUGCCCGGCAGCCAGAAGGGCGUGCUGGUGGCCCCUGGAGGCCUGGCGCUGCCGGCCUACGGCGAGGACGGGGCCCUGGAGCACGAGCGCAUGCAACAGCUGGAGCACGGCGGCCUGCAGCCAGGCCUGGUCAACCACAUGGUGGUGCAGCAUGGCCUGCCGGGCCCCGACAGCCAGUCGGCCGGCCUGUUCAAGACCGAACGCCUGGAGGAGUUCCCGGGCAGCACCGUAGACCUACCCCCCGCGCCUCCGCUCCCUCCUCUGCCGCCGCCCCCAGGCCCCCCACCCCCUUACCAUGCCCAUGCGCACCUUCACCACCCGGAGCUCGGGCCCCACGCCCAGCAGCUGGCCUUGCCCCAGGCCACCCUGGACGACGACGGGGAGAUGGACGGCAUCGGGGGCAAGCAUUGCUGCCGCUGGAUCGACUGCAGCGCCCUGUACGACCAGCAGGAGGAGCUCGUGCGGCACAUCGAGAAGGUCCACAUCGACCAGCGCAAAGGGGAGGACUUCACUUGCUUCUGGGCCGGUUGCCCUCGAAGAUACAAGCCCUUCAACGCCCGCUAUAAACUGCUGAUCCACAUGAGAGUCCACUCUGGGGAGAAGCCCAACAAGUGUACGACUGCCAUUUCUGUACCUGCAGAACCCGUAGGCCCUGACUGAAGAAUUCACUCCAGAGCACAUCCUCCUGUGACUCUCGCCAAAGUGUUUGUAACCAACCGUUAAAUUCAGAUGGUUCCUCUGAGCUUGGGAAAAUACGUUUUAUUGCUCUGUGCCUUUUGAGAGCUUGGAAAGGUGGAGGUCUUGUGGAGUUGUGGAAACAUCUGUAGAGUACGUUGUUUGCAGGCUCUGGUCUGUGCUGAGAAUAGAGCAGUGACCGUGAAGGAUGAGAUCUCUGCCCUCACAGAGCUGAUGUUCUGCUGGUGAGUGUGGACAGGCUUCCUGCUGUGCCACCAGAGAGUCCUGUGACUUUGGGUGGGUGGUUAACCUCUCCAAGCUAUUGUGUCUUCAUCUUCAACUCUUCAUCUUCGAAGGAGUUAGACCUUUUGAAGGCUUUGUGCUUAACUCAUACAUUUUUUAUUUGUUCUUCUUUCUCAUUCAAAUAGCAAGAAGCUAUUCAAAGAGUAACUUGACUUUUUGUUUUGACCUUGAAGUAAAUUCUUGGAGGCUUUUAUUUGAUAAACAAAACAGAACAAAACUCAAAGCCUGAAGCAAACUGUCUUUACCUCAGGAACAAAAACAACAGAUUGCCGUGUUUGAUGGUCUGUGCAACAUAAAGAAAGGCAGAGCUUUAGAAGAACAUUGGAAAUCUCAGCAGUCUACAGUUCGCCAAUGGUGUCACUAAUUGGGUGGCCUCUGGGGCCAUAUUCCUUUCUCUUCAUGUGGCUUUGCUGCUAGUUGCUAUCCAGAAUUUUUUUUUUUUUUUUUUAUGAAGAAAGAAAACAAGUAGGCACUGAGUCUGGCUCUUCCUCUGUCUUGUAGCUCUUUUUUUUUUUUUUAGCCUUGAGCACCAUUGAGACAUUUAUCCACUAGAGAAAGACCUGCUAUGUGCCUGGGACUGUUUUAGGCUUAGGAGAUAUUCUGUCGAACAAGACAGGAACAGUCCUGCCCUCGUGGAGUUUAAGUCUAGAAAGGAAGAGAAGUAGACAAUUAACUAGUGAAUGAUUAAAUAAUUUGGGGGAAUCUGAAAGUGCUGUGAAGAGAUUGAAACAAUGAUGUCAGCAAAGUGCCUGGGGUGGGAGGAGGAGCUUUGCAACUUGCUUGACCAAAAGGUUCUGUCUCAGGAGGUGGUCAGUGAGCUGGGCCUGGAUGAUAAGGAGAAGCUAUUGCUUGAUCCCACAAUGGCCCCUCAUGCUAGUUAAUACCGGUUAUAAAAUUAAACAUGAGGCUGGGCGCUGUGGCUCACGCCUGUAAUCAUAGCCCUUUGGGAGGCCAAGGCAAGUGGAUUGCUGGAGGCCAAGAGUUCGAGACCAGCUGGGCCAACAUGGCAAAAUCUUGUCUCUACCAAAAAAUACAAAAAUUAGCCAGAUGUGGGGGUGUGCGCCUGUGGUCCCAGCUACUCAGGAGGCUGAGGCAGGAGAAUUGCUUGAACUUAGGAGGCAGAGAUUGCAGUGAACUGAGAUCAUGCUACUGCACUCCAGGCUGGGCAACACAGCGAGACUCUUUCAAAAAAAUAAAAAUUAAAAUACUAAAUUAAACAUGAAUGAAAAAUGGCGUAACUGCUGUGGAACACCAUUUGGCAGUUCCUCCAUAGGUUAAACAGAAUUACUAUGUGACCCAGCAAUUCUACUCCUAGGUAUAUAUACCUAAAAUAAUUAAAAACAGACAUUUAAACAAAAACGUUUACAUGAAUGUUUUUAGUAGCACUGCUCAUAAUAGGCAAAAGAUGGAAACAACUCAAAUGUCCAUCAGUGGAUGAAUGGAUAAACAAAAUGUGGUAUAUCCAUAUAGUGAAAUUUUAGAAUAAAGUUCUGAUACAUGCUGCAACAUUGAUGAACCUUGAAAACAUUGUACUAAGUGAAAAAAGCUAGGCACAAAAGGCCACAUAUUGUAUCAUUCAGUUUCUACGACAUGUCCAGAAGAGGUAAAUCUAUAGAGACAGAAAUCCGACUAGUGGUUGACUAGGGGCCAGGGUGUGAGUGGGGAAUGAGGAGUGGCUAAAUGGCUAUAGGGCUUUCUUUCAGGGUAAUGAAAAUGUUCUGGAACUAGAUGGUGGUGAUAGUUGUACACCAUUAUGAAUGCAUUUAAUAUCAUGAAGUAUGUACUUUUAAAUGGCUAAAAUGGUAAAUGUUAACAUGAAUUUUACCACAAAAAAAAAUUAAACCAAUUGUGAUGUUUGACACGAGUCUUUAUGAAGCAACAUUUAUAUAUACUUGAAAAAUAUCCUGAAAACGAAAUGUACCUAUCUGUCUUAGUUCUUUAUUUCAGGAGGAUGGGGAGAAAGUUUUAUUUGGUAUUUAUUUAGGCCACUCCCUCUGAAAGAAGGCUUUCAUGGACUUACCAAAAUAUAACUGAACCUAAACACAGGUAUGCAAAUAUUCAGGUGUGCACAUCUCUCCAUUGAUUCUUUUAAGCCCCAAAUUAUUUAGAAGUGAACAGGAUGUGUUUUAUACCCGGGCCUCUCCCAAUGCACUCUAAUCUGUAAUUGUGUUCUACAAAUGAGCAAUGAGACAGAUUCAGCCCCUGUAUAUACGCAUGAUACAUAGACAUUCGACAUGUAUGUAUCAUCUAUAAACGUUAGUACCUUCCACUGUUCCAGCACCUAAAAUAAAUACAAAUGGCAAAAAGCCCACCUUUGACUGAACAUUAAAAUAUUAGCCACAGCAGUUGUGCCCUAUUUGUUAGUGGAGUUUGGUGUGUCAUCCAUCUGACAUAUGGGAGAAAUUGGUGAAAAUACUGCAGCCUAGAAUAGUGUUUGAUGACAUCUGAAGAGUUUUCAAACUUCUGGUAAAAAUUAUUGCUAUGUUCUUUUUUAAAAACAAACAAACAAAACUCAGUUUUCAAAUAAUAUGCAUUUAGUUUCUCAAGUCUUUAUGACCAUGUUCUUUCUUUGAAUUACAUGAAUAAAAUACUAGUUAGGCCUCUUUGGGCUUUUUGUUUUUUCUUUCAGUUCCUCUGAUCCACAUAGUUAUUAGGAGGUGGAGAUAUGUUUGGCUACAUUUUUCAAGGGAUGGAUUUUGAUACAUUUAGGCUUAGAUACAAAGCUCUAUACCCGACUGUCUUAGAAAAUGUUGAGACUAUAGCAAUCUCCAGCAGUCCAGAAUGUUCCCGAUAGCUUCUGUCUACCUAACCACUUGUAAGUGGCAACCCCCUAUCCCCGCCCCUGCCACACACACCUUUCUUUUUCCUUCAGAUACUUUUCUACCACAUUCCACAUUCGAAAUAAGCAAUUGAAUGUCUUGUUAAGCCAUGUUUGAAUUUCCUCAUAAACACACACGUGAGAGAAGAGAGGCUUAGUCUGCUCUGUUUGUUUGAGGCUCAUUGUCUGCUUCCAUUUUGACCCAGUUUCUUUAGGGGCUGGGAGAACAAGGAGAAUUUUAGGCCUCACGGGAGCUUAUCAAUGGAUGCUUUCAGACAGUCCUCUGAAACAUGUGCCUUAGUAGUAAUUAAUUUGCCUAGGAUCCUACAUUCUUCAGAAGGAGUUUAUUGUUCUCCAACAGGAGGAAAAAUAAAUCUUUGUAGUUUAUUGUGAAACCUUCAGCUUCCCCCAACUGUGAGGACCCUGACUAUCAGGUUUAGGAUUUCACCUGCAGGUGUGAAGGCUUACACUUUUUAUCUCCUCUUACGUGGAGGCCCAUCUCUGAUGGGGAGGGGUGAGAGCCUAACCAGUCUUGUAAAAGUGAUGCCAGUGACUUUCAGUGGACUCUAGUGUUUGAAGGCUUUAAAAAGUUAGUACUGAAAGAUCAGAAUCCCACAGGAAAGGUAUAAAAACAAUAAAGGCCCCUAACAUGACAUAGCGUGUUCUGUACAGAGAUAUAUACUCCACAUUCUUCAAACAUUCCUCGGAAGAUUUUUUUAAAAUUACUUUUAUUUUUAUUAUUAUACUUUAAGUUCUAGAGUACAUGUGCACAAGCUGCAGGUUUGAUACAUGGGUAUACAUGUGCCAUGUUGGCUUGCUGCACCCAUCAAAUUGUCAUGUACAUUAGGUAUUUCACCUAACGCUAUCCCUCCCCCAGACCCCCACCCACCAACAGGCCCUGGUGUGUGAUGUUCCCCGCCCUGUGUACAAGUGUUCUCAUUGUUCAAUUCCCACCUGUGAGUGAGAACAUGCGGUGUUUGGUUUUCUGUCCUUGCGAUAGUUUACUGAGAAUAAUGGUUUCCAGCUUCAUCCAUGUCCCUGCAAAGGACAUGAACUCACCCUUUUCUGUGGCUGCAUAGUAUUCCAUGGGGUAUAUGUGCCACAUUUUCUUAAUCCAGUCUAUCAUUGCUGGAUAUUUGGGUUGGUUCCAAGUCUUUGCUAUGGUGAAUAGGCCGCAAUAAACAUACGUGUGCAUGUGUCUUUAUAGCGGCAUGAUUUAUAAACCUUUGGUUAUAUACCCAGUAAUGGGAUGGCUGGGUCAAAUGGUAUUUCUAGUUCUAGAUCCCUGAGGAAUUGCCACACUGUCUUCCACAUGGGUUGAACUAGUUUACAGUCCCACCAACAGUGUAAAAGUGUUCCUAUUUCUCCACAUCCUCUCCAGCACCUGUUGUUUUCUGACUUUUUAAUGAUCACCAUUCUAACUGGUGUGAGAUGGUAUCUCAUUGUGGUUUUGAUUUGCAUUUCUCUGAUGGCCAGUGAUGAUGAGCAUUUUUUCAUGUGUCUGUUGGCUGCAUAAAUGUCUUCUUUCGAGAAGUGUCUGUUCAUAUCCUUUGCCCACUUUUUGAUGGGGUUGUUUGUUUUUUUCUUGUAAAUUUGUUUGAGUUCUUUGUAGAUUCUGGAUAUUAGUCCUUUGUCAGAUGGGUAGAUUGCAAAAAUGUUCUCCCAUUCUGUAGGUUGCCUGUUCACUCUGAUGGUCAUUCCUCCGAAGAUUCUUAUGCAGGAAGCUUAUUCCUAUGUGUGCGCAAGUGUGUUGGAGGUGGGGAUAUAUGUAUGAAAGAGAAUGAAGGAAAGAAUCAGACUACGAAUAGCUCAGUACACGACACUCCUGCCGGCAUCUGUGGGCUGUGGGCAUUGGCAGUAGUUGCAGCCUUUAACAGCCAGCCUGGCAUUGGCACUGACCAAUUGGAAUGGGCAUCAACUAAUGGAGCAAGGUCCUUGAUGGCCCAUUUCAUGCUAGGCUUUUAUCCUUUAACAAUCACGUUGUAGGGAGGUGAGGAAGGGGCCCUGCAGAAGUAGUCCAGAUGGCCAGGCCAGUAGCAGGGGGAUCUUAGGUAUCAAGGCAGAGGUUAUUUACCAACCAGUAUGGUUGUAUUUGAGUAUUUUGACAAGCAGUACACUGGCUGAAGCUCUGGAAAUCUCUCUGUAUCCUAGACUUCUGGAGUAGUUCCUAUCCAGGUGCAGCUGUUGUUGUUAUUAGAUGUGUGUUUUCUUUCUUGCAUUGUGUGUUUGUGUGAUAGUUUGCUCAGACAUCAUUGGUGUGUGUCUGAACUGCUAUUUGGUUAGAACCUCACCAUUUGUUCUUAGCCCUCUCUGUAUGUCCAUGGUGUUCAGUCCAGAUUGAGGUCUGCUGACUUGGUUGGAUCCCCAAAUAAUUUCCUGUCCUGCCACGUGUUGGUGACUAUUUCAAAGUGAAAGCAUGCAGUAGGGUCACUGGCAUUCCAGAGAUGGUUGUUAGGAGGUCUACAUUGCCUGUUUCUAGAAAAGCGCUCAAAUGUUGGAAGUAACUAAGUUGUUGGUCAGAUAUUUGUGCAGGAAUCCUAACAGGUGCAUAGGCUAGGCCUAGUCACCUGAUGGGUGGCUGGAAAGACAGCCCUUGAGAGGGGUGAAAUUACUGAGAAAAUUUGCUUCAUCUGAGCCCCACAGAGAGGACUUCAGUGCUGGAAGAGAUGCUGCCACCUAUUGAUCAUGGUCUUAAAAGAUGCUUUUGUGCUCUCUUUGAAGAGAUGCUUCUGUCUUCAUUAGGUCAUUGGCUUCAGAGCAAUUUGACGCAAUUUAAAAAUAAGCACACAGUUGAAUACCAUAAUGUGGUUAAGCCAGCUGUUUCUGACCGUGCUAGCUACUUUUUUUUUCUAUUUAUGAGAAUGGCUUAUAUUAUGCACAUACUGAGCCAUGGCAUGGCUAUAUGAUAGCCCCAUAUAAUAUCAGCAUUUAAGGUGGACUGUUUAAAAAGAUCCACAGGGUAAUAAGUUUCCAGCAGGAUCCCUUACAGUGUGUGAACCAUCUAACAGCUUUUUGCCCUUCCAUCUUCUGCUAAACAUGUUUUCUUGAUCCUCACACAUAUCAUUCUGAAUUUAAAAAUACCAUUUACUUUCCUUGGUUUCAUUUAAAUGUUGCAUUAUGUUUAACUAUAGCCAGCCCUACAUAAUAAAAUUUUCUAAAAGGUCAUUACCCCUCACUCUUCUUCAGGGGUCGGAUAAAUUCAGUGUGAACACACAGAACUGCAGUAAAUGGGGGCAAAAUGCCAGUUUUAUUUAGGGCUCUCCAAUCAUGGGUUCAAUUGGAGAACACAGUGAGGCCCCUUUCCCCACUGCCUAAGCCCUGAGUCUUGCCCACACUUCUUACCCAGAGAUUGUUGGAAAAGUAAGAACCAGAGAACAAAGACCUCCUUAGGCCUACCAGCUGGUGAAGUAGAUUUCUGCUGUCCCAACAGAGUUCAUCUCACAAAAGUUUACUGGCCUUGCCUACACUAAUUGCAAUUAUUUUCCUAUGUAACCGAAAAAGCAGACAGAGAGGUCAGGAAUGUUGGCUUUGGAGCCAUAACACCCAGGUUCAUGUCUUUCCCAGAACAUUCCUGAAUCAACUAGGGUUCCCUUUUCUGUGCUGGCAUGGGGUAGCACACUGAGCCGACUCCCACCUCUUUUCAUACUGACAUCGUUAUAUUACAGUUUUUUCUUUCCCUAGAUUGUGAGCUUCUUCAGGUCAGGAACCAUGUGUAAGUCACUUAUGCAUCUCUAGCUCCCAGCAUAAUAGGUACUUUAUUAUUUGUGAAGCUAAAAUGCAAAGUAAGUGAACCAGAAAGGGUAGGUCACAAGGUGUGGAUUUAAGUUUGUUUGUAAUUCAGAGCAGUAACAGGUUUUUGAAAUUAGUGAAAUGAACAGAAUUAGAAUAUGGGUCUAAAAAAGUAAUAUAAAAAUAAAGAUUCUUAAGAUUUAAAAGGACCUUAAAAGAUUACCCAAUUGUAUUAGUCCGUUUUCACACUACUAUCAAGAUACUACCUGAGACUGGGUAAUUUAUAAAGGAAAGAGGUUUAAUUGACUCACGUUCUGCAUGACUGGGGUGGCCUCAGGAAACUUACAAUCAUGACAGAAGGGAAAGUAGUCACGUCUUAGCUGGUGGCAGGCGAGAGACAGAGCGAAGGGGGAAGAGCCCCUUGUGAAACCAUCAGCUCUCAUGAGAACUCACUCACUAACACAAGAACAGCAUGGGGGAAACAGCCCCCAUGAUCCAGUCACCUUCCAGCAGGUUUCUCCCUCAACUCAUGGGGAUUACAGUUCCAGGUGAUAUUUUGGUGGGGACAUAGAGCCAAACAAUAUCACCAACUCAGCAACCCAUUUUGAAGUCUACACUCCGACAACUUUCCCAUUAGUGUUUGUUGAGACUUUGAGCAUCUGCCAGGGCUUAAACUGUUUUCACAUUGAGGUAAAAUAUCCUUUACAGCUUUCAUCCCUAAUUGUGUCCUCUGGCAAUACCUAGAUGAAGUAUUGCCUCUCUUCAGUUUUCAUUUAUUUGAAGAAGAAUUGCCAUGUCUCUCAACCCAUACUUGCCAAGUAAACAUGCCUAGUUCAUUCAGCCAUUCUUCAUAUAAUACAAUUUAGAGUUCCUGCAUUAUCCUGGUAGAGGAACUCUAAAUAUAUUCCAGUGAAUGUACUUCCCUCAAAAAAUGCAACGCUAGAAGUGAAGAUAAUACUUCAAGUAUGGCACAGAGUAGAAAAGAUUUAUUACCUACCUAAUUCUAAAAAUCACAUGCACAUUAAGUACAACUUAUCGUAUUAGCUUCAUUGAUUGCUGGCCCCACCUUUGACCCAUGUUCAGUUUUCUGUUGAUGAACACAGAGCAUUUCUGUGUGCUGCUGCUUAAGUCAUGUAUCUCUCAGCCCCUCCUUAUAGGGUUGUUUAUUUGGGCCCCAAAGUGUUAUAUCCUGCUAGAUCUAACCCACCUCUCAUGCCUGCCAACCCUCUCUUUGGAUCCAUACUGUACCAUUCAGGGUCUUUACUGUUUUUCUCAGCACUGUGCCUGUGAAGAUUUGGUAGGGUUGCCUUUACUGUCUUCACAUAGGUGCAUGAUGAAAAUGUUCAACUGGGCAGGUCAAGAAUAGAGCCCUGUGGUAAGCUACUAGAAUCCUCUCUUAAGGUGAGUAUCAACUUUGAAAACAGUUUAUAACAAGUUUUACACCCCCCUCUAUAAUUUAUAAGACUGCCAUAAGAGACCUUAUAAAAUACAUUGUUGAAGUCCAUAUUUUGGUACAGCAAUAUAAAUGAAGGGAAAAAUGAGCUUAGGCUGAUGUGGCCAAUUCUGAGUGAAAUUAAAAUUUGCUGCCUCCUGGCAGUUGCACUUUUUGUUCUGUCUUGUCAUGAGCAGCCUAAUAAACCAUUUAUGAUUUCCCCCCCGAUCUCCCAAGGUGACCGACCUCUAUAUAAUUUUUAGAAUCUUUCUUCUUCAGUUUAAAAGUAUGAAUGACAUUUGCCAGUCCUCCAACUUUUGGCACAUCUUUCAUUUUCCAAGAGUACUCAAAGAUAUCUGACGGGGCGGAACAUUAGUGAUCUCUGUUGCAAGGACUCAUAAUAUCUAGAGCUGUGAUUGCGAGACUGUGUUUAAUUUCACCUUCAGCCUCUUGUCUGAUUCUUUCCAGGCAUCUGCUGUUGGGGCCAGGACUUCUUCUUUUUCCAAGUUGUUACAUUGCAUGUACAAAAGAAAAGUUCAGCUGGGUGGGGUGGCUCACAUCUGUAAUGUCAGCACUUUGGGAGGCUGAGGUGGGAGGAUCACGAGGUCAGGAGUUCGAGACCAGCCUGGCCAACAUGGUGAAACCCAUCUCUACCUUAAAAAAAAAAAAAAAUUAGCCAGGUGUGGUGGUGUGUGCCUCUAAUCCCAGCUACUCGGGAGGCUGAGGAAGGAGAAUUGCUUGAACCUGGGAGGUGGAGGAUGCAGUGAGCCGAGAUCGCACCACUGCACUCCAGCCUGGGUGAUAGAGCGAGAUUCCGGCUCAAAAAAAAUUUUUUCAUUUUUAUAGCAAAAAGUUCAGAACACUUCAUCUUCCUGCAGCUUUUUAGUUACGUGAAAUCCACAAGGUCCAGUGUGUACAUCAGUUUCCUUCAUUUGCAAGGGGACCGUCUUCAAGUAAUAGGGCUUACGAUAAGGAUGCAAUAUCAAUAUGGCCAAAAUGGCAACUUGGAAACACAAAAUUGAAUCAGUAAAUGUCAGGACUUGGAAUUCAAAGAUCUAAGGCAACUCUAGGUGCUAGGUUGUCUGGCCACUGCUGUUGGCUGCAGUUGAGUGACUUCCACCCUAGUCCUAUGCUAAAAACAGACUCUGCUCUGUUCUCUGCCUUGUUUUUUAUGCCUGCACUACCAAACAGCUUUCUGAGUCCUCCCUUCCUCGGAAUUUACAUCUGCCCUUGCUUUUGGCUUAAUCAAAAGUUUUUCCUCACCCACUGCAUUCUGUAGUCUGUUUCUUACUCAUUCUAUUAUCCUGGGGGACUUUCAAGAUGGUGUCUGGAAAAAUUUAGGAAUGGAUCUGCCCAAAGAUAAAAAGAAAGUGAAGAGUCUGUGUUAGUCCCAGGUUUUUGCUUUUCUUUUCAAAGAAAUAUGAGAAAGCAUGCUAGUGUCUCUAACUCUGUGACAGUACUGUGAGCAGUCACCCUCAGUCAUGCCCAUGACCUCUUUCUGAGGUAGUGGUUCACCUUGUAGACCACCAGGUCUACUGUACCCAACCCAGACUGCAAUGUGCACCUGACCCAAAGACAGUCACUCCAUGUGCUGGCCAGCAAAAAGCUCUUUCCCACAUAGGAUAAGAUGGACCCAUUGGAUUCCUUCUCUGUGAAUAAUUUUCACUGAAAAAUAGGAAUAGGACCAGGCGUGGAGUAGCAGGAACAGAAAAUUAAAGAGAAAUGAGAGACUAUGAGAGACCAGAGAGAGACUAUGUGUUAAUUUUCCUAAGGGAAAGGAACAAUCAGGAAAACAAAUGUUGACGUGCUAAGGGGCGUUGGGAGAUUACUUAAUAUCUCCUACAGUCUUCGUACAGAUCUGUAUAAUCAUAUGCAUAAAUGCUUUAUGUCUAUUUAGUCGAACUUGGCACUAGGGGAUGGAGAGUGUCUGGUUUCACAGGUAGAGUUAAGAGCCACACACUGUUCCGAAGACUUUGAUCUUUCUUUUGUUGUAAGAACUUCAUUCUCCUGUUGAACAGACUCCCUCCCCAUGUCCUUUCUGAUGGGCAUCCUCAGAAGGUUGCUCAGCUUCUCUGGGACACUGAAGGUGUCUGCCAGUUUUCUCUUCUGUGCCGGACCCUAUUGGUGAUGUUUGCCUGCUCUGCCCUCUUGGCCCUUACCUGUGCUCUUGACAAGGCCCAUCAUAUUGCCUUCCAUUGUUGGUGACAACAGCCGGCUGUGGGUGCUGGCCAGUGCUGCAGGUGUCAGGUUCUGCUGCUCUUGCAGCUGAUAUAUCUGGGAGCCCCCAACCCAAGACUUGCAUUGUGUUCUCCAGAACUACAAGUGAACUCUGAAGCUGCAUCCUGUUCUUGUCUUCAUAGGAAAUAAUUACUCUUCUCUCUUUUGUGUUACUCAGUCACAUUAUUCUAAAGAGGUACUGGGUCAGUUCCCAGUAGCUCAAAGAUGGUGUGAAAACAGAUCUUUCUGUUAGUUUUUCAGGCUUAUUCACAUGUCCAUGGCUGUUGGGACUUGUAGAGAAGAAGGUUUUCCUGGGAGCAAACUCAGCAGUAGAAUAGUGUGCUCAAAACCACCUCCCCAGCCCUCCAAUAACUGAGUCAUUGAGACAAAACUCAUGGUGCUGACCUUCUCCUUCUUUAGGAUAUGAUUUAAAGGCCCCUUCCCAGCCCUUCCUACAGACUGACUGAUGGAGCCUUCAGCCUGCCAGUCACCCCAAACCAGCCGUACCUGAUUAUCUCCUGGGAAUCCUACCACAGCUCAAUCAGAACUGCUCCCCACCCUCACCCCACCUGCCUUAAUUCUUAGAAAAUACAUAAAAAACUCAGUGUACCUCACCCUGAUCUCCCACCUCAAAACUAAGAAAACUGGAUUUCUUGCUCAACACUCUACACUUCAUACUUGAAAAAAAAAUUAAUUCUGACAGAACCACCUCUGGCCCCUUGCCAAAGACGUAAAGUCUCACUGAAAGUGAUUGGGAGGAAAGGAACAAAUGGAUGCUUAAAGGGAUUAAAAUGCAGGAGUUAAAUUGGGACCUUGAGUGGGGCUGUGGGAAGGGGAGGGGCUGGGAAGCUGUGAAUGCAGAGAACCACAGCUGAGAGCAUUGUGGCUCCGGGGGAGAAAAACCAUUUUGGGUUCUUAGUAGAAGAAUAGCCAUUUCUUUUGAUAUUUCCAAGAUUGCCACUCUUGGGGUUUGCGCUCUUUUUCACUGUACCUUUUUUUUUUUUUUUCUUUUCAAGCAAGCUCUAAUGACUUGGCGUCCUGGCACAUAGCUGCAUUCUGCUCAUAAUAAUGUGUACUUUCAAGUUUUUACUCAAACUCAAUAUAAUUUCCUUUAGAAAAAUGUUUUUGAGAAACACAGUAUUAAAUCAAGAAAGCCCUUGCUGCUUUUAUUGUCACUAAAAUCAUAUAUUGUUUUCCAAAGAAUACUGCCAUUUGUUUAUAUUUCCCUACAGUUUUUGUUUUUGGGAGUUUUGUUUUGUUAUAGUGGCAGCUGAAGUGAUUUUGAGUGUUUGCAGCAUGAUGUUAAUUAACCAAAUGUUUCAACCUGGAACUUUGAACACCUGGGCUUACAUAAAUUGCUCAGAAUCAGUGUGGAAAUCUUCGGAACAGUGGAUGUAGAAGAUUUGGGGUAAAACAGGCACUAGAUGGUGAGGGGUUUUAUGCUCUACUCAUUCUUUACGCAAAAUAAAAACAGACGAGUAAGUGUUGGCCUCUUUGGAACAGAUGAUUCCCAGCAGCAGUUGGCAUGCUUUAUGUACUCAUGGGUUAACCGGAAGCAGCUCUCAGAAUAUCCAUUUUAAUGAAGAUAGCUUAGGUUUAGUCUAUGUUUGGCUGACAGUUAACACUGUUCCCAUUUCACUUCUCUAUUCUGCUGACCCUUGGGCUUGAUAAUGUUUACAUCUUGGAUACUUGCAAAUGAAGAAUCAAGGCUGGCCAUGGGAAUUACUAGGGUGUCAGAGUGAAAUUUUGGUACCCAAAUCUCUCCACUCAUCCUUCCUUCCUUCAGGAAGCUCCUGACCAAGAGAUUGUUGACUAAAGAAAAAAAAAACAAAAACCCAAGCUUUUGAAAUGAUUAACGUGCGUUCUAUUCAGAAAUCUUAUUGAGGACUGUAGAUGAGGCCUGUAGCUUGAGAGUUGCUCUCUUGAGAGGUUCUGUCAGCACAGUUUCAGCUCACUGCGUAUAUACAGGUGGUGGAGGUUCAGGACAUGCAAAAUCACAUCAAACUUGUCCAGAAUUACACUAAAGCAGAGUCAUAUCAAGGUUUGGGCAUAAGAGUACACCUGGAUAUAGGUUACAGAAGCAUAAUCACUAAGACUGUCAGAUAUUGUCUUAUGUGCAGAAAAAGGCAAGGACUAGGGUCAUUUAUCUUUUAAGGAAAUAGUGACUCAAGCAAGAGACAUGAAGUGGGGUUGGGUGUUCUACCUGGUUUUAUCUUCAGAACAUCUUUCUGGAGAGCUUCACGUUUUCAGAGAGUCAGGGACUUUGUGACGUUAGAUUCCAGAGAACAGAAAUAAAACAUGCCAUCUUACAUUUGUUACUUUGUCUCACAGAGCAUAGGCAAACAAGAACCAUACUGAUUAGGAAACGAAGCACCGUUUUAUGAACAAUUAAGUAGGCACCUGAUAACAUCACAGAGACACACACACACUAAAAAUGGAGCUCUGGUAAGGCAGAAUUGAGUCUCAAUGGUGGUGCCCAUGAAGUUGACCCAAGCUUUUUUCCACCAAGUCUAAGGUGCAAAAACUAAAACAGAUUGAGAUAGUUGAUUUGCCUAAAGCAAGGCUUCUCAAAAGCAGCAUUAAUGACACUGGGGGCAAGAUAGUUCGUUUCAGCAGAGGCUGUUCUGUGCACUGUAGGAUGUUUGGCAGUUUCCCUUAUCCCUAGUUGGUAGAGGGAAAUAGAGGCCGGUAGCAAACUUCCACUCCCACCCCCUUGUUUUAACAACCAAAGAUAUCUCCAGUCAUUGCUAGACAUCCCCCGGGGCUUUUAAUAAGCUUCCCAGGGAUUCCCAUGUGCAGUCAUAUUUGAGAAACAGUGUUUUAAAGAAGUACAGUCACUACUGGACAUGGCCAAAAUGCCUGCCUUGCAGAUGUCCUGUGUAAUGAACACCUUCUUGAUGGUACUCACUCCACAUAACUAUCCUUCACUUUCAAAGUUUAGCAUGCAUUAGAAUCACGAGGUGGGACAGGAUUAGAAUGUUGAGAAAGAAAUCUUUCUCCUUCCCUGGGUCUGGAGUGGGUCCUGAUGUUUUGUAUUUCAAACAAGUUUCCAAGCAGUGCUGAUGCUGCUGGACCAGGAGACCACCUUUGAGAACCACUGUUGAUGACCUUCACUUCAACUCUUACCUAAAGAACAAUGACCCAGUUGACCCAGUUGACAGCACCACUUGAAGACUGUGGUAGAACGAUCUACUGAACACCUCAUUCCAUCACCUCUUUUCAUCUUUUUAUAGUGUUUUCUCCUUUUCUCCAUCUUUUAUAACUCACUAUCCACUUAGUUCCACUGAAGAAACUCUGUCUUUAUCGUCCACAUUAAUAGUUCUCCAAAGUGCUGGGAGUUCCCGUUCAGAUUUUUUCCAUUCCUUCUAUAUCCUUAUUGAUUGAAUAUUUUUCUUCACUUGCUUGCAUUAAAGAUUUUAGGAAAAGACCUAAAAUCUGGUUUUGUUGUUCAGAUUGUCCUUAUUUGUGAUAUACUAUCAGCGGGGAUGUCUUCCUUUUCUAUCGUAAAUGUAGCACGCUGUAAUAGUUUGUUAUUGAAAGAGACUUUGGGAGUUAAUUUAAAAACCUAACAGCCAUUUUCAAACAAUGAAUUAAUAAUUUUUGACAGAAAACCUUUGUAACUAGGGGACUAUAUAUUCAAUGUAGCAGGUUUUUUGUUUUUUGUUUUUUUUACCUUGUGAAGUAAAAUGUUUUGUAAUUCAGACAUAUUAUUUAAAAUGCUUUGAAGUUUGCAAAACCCUUUGAAGACCAAGGCUGUGAUUUACAUGUCCCCAUUUAUAUUUUUAUUAAAAUCACCACCCCUCCAUAAAUAAAGGUAUUAAUGGGUAAAUAUUUGGCCAGUUAAGUACCAGGACUGUGUAGGGGGCUUUCCUGCAGAUGGGCAGAGGAUGUAAUUUCAUUAAACAGGAGGUCUCAGUUACCCUCUGUUUGGAAUCCACUGAAGUAGGACUUCUCUUGGCUCUCCUCUUAAGACUCAAAUCUUCCCAAACAGUUUUGGCCUCCACAUUUGUGAUGCACUGGCCUUGGGCUUGGCAUUGACCCAUUGGCCUUGUCGAUCCUCCAAUUUAUACUGUGCACUUAAAUUCUAAAAUGAUACUUUUGCUCCAUCUGCUUCUAACUUGAGUGCUCUAACUCCUGUAGUACUUGACCAUUGUGACAUUAUACUGUAGUAGUCAUUGAAAAACACUCAACAUCUCCCAGACAUUUCUAUGACCCUAACAGAAUCUGGACCGAUUGUAGAGGAAAACACAUAGAUCUUAGAAAAUACAGUGGGAAAGAGCACUGGCUGGGAGCCAGGCAGGCUCUGGGUCAGGCUUUGGCACUAAAUAGUGGUGUUUCCUUGGACGAGUCACUUCUCUUACCUGGCCUGUAUUUUUAUGGCCUAGAAAAUUGAGGGAGUUAGAUGAGGUGGUCUGUAAGCUCCUUUUUGAGGCUGCCGUCCUGUGUUUGUGAAGUUUUGUAUUUUGUGGGCUGGAGACCCAUCAGAGCAGCUUGUUUCCAAGAAGCACAGGCCUCUUUCCACAUAGCUCACAGGAAAUACAUUGUCUGGAAGAGAGAGAGAGAGAUGCUUGGAUACCUGUAGAAAAUGUUUGGUGGCUUCUCUAUUUUGCUAUUCAGUGGCUAGAUAAUACUGCAUUGGACAGCUGGGAAAAAUAAUUUUUUUUCAGUCAAGUCUUCAAAUUUUGGUCCUCGGCACCAAUUACAUAAUAUAUGCAGAAAUACCUUUAUGAAUAAAUAUGUAGGACCCUCUCCAGAGAAUAACCAGGUGCCCUAUUAAAUUCCAUAUGAAAUGGGUAGAGUGUGGAACCACCCUAGGUGUGAAAAGAGUCCUUAAAGUGUUCCCAAAGGGCAGGAUUAUAGCAACGUAUGGUGCCCAGGCUUAUUACAUUGGUUUUCCUUUUUUAUUCUCCCUCCUCAAGUUUGUAAGAGACGGAUGAUUCCUAUUGUUGUGGCAAGCUGCUCAGCUUUACCCAACGGUUCAUAGUGAGAGAAGACAUGGGGAGGGCAGUUAGUUCCUCAGUUGGGGAAAUUAGACUGCCUUGGAGGUCACUGGGGGCAAAGGUGAUCAGAGUUAUGCGGAGCCCAGUCUGUCAUCUUCAUGAUGUUUCUACAGACAGGGAUACUUGAAUGCACAGUGUUGAAUGCAUUUAAAGGCUGGAUCCACACAUUUAAGAAAUCAGGAUUAAGGAAGCUGUACAGAUGUAAACUUUGAAGAAAACAAUGAAAAAAAGAAUAGUGGAGAGCUGAAUACGUGUGGCCAAACUAUGUCACUUACCAAAGGGCCAGUCAUCAUCUUUUAUAACAUGCUAGCACAGUGGUUUGCAGAAUGUAUUCUCAUGCCUGCUUUCAGGAUAAAAACGUUAAAGAGACAUGCCUGGGAAAUUCCUUUUCCUUUUAAUCAGGAUAAAGUGGCCUGUUGAGGCCUGGGAAAGUGUAUUGGAUUUCACCUUUGAUCUCCCAUACGUCAGUCUCUUUACAAGUGGUCAUUUCUCUGAAAGGUACAAGCUGGGACUAUUUGGCAUUGAGUUCCAGAAUGGCCUUUAUCAUCUUGAUGACAAUUUUUCCAAUUUCUUUAACAGUUUAUUCAGUUGUAAAACUACAGUGACUCAUGUAAUUAGAGGUUUCCCUCUGUGUCAACAGAGAGGAUUUUUGGAACCAACAAGUUGGACAAGUUUCCUACCACACUUCAAAAGAAGUAGUUAAUCAUGGGAUAAUAUUUUUAGGAUGUCGAAACUGGAAUAUGGCUGGCUGCUAAUCAUCCCCAAAUAAAACUCUUGAUUAAUUACAAAUAAAUUAAUCCAAGAGUGACAAAAUUUACUUGGGCCUCAUUGAAGUUUUACCAGGUUGCUUCCUCCAAGCCAGGUGAACAGGAAGAGGGGAAAGAUGUUCUUCUCCCUCAUUAAAGUUCCACUUAAAUAAAUAAAAACAAAAACACUCUGAACUCACAAAGACAGAUGGGCUAUCUUGUAAAACAUUUUAUCCAAUGAAGUGAUUUUUUUUUUCCUUUCCUGGAUUUUGUAUCUCCCCUGAAUGUGGGCAGCUGAAAAGUGUGUAUAAAAUAUUCCCAGGAAAACACCAAAGUGAAAUUUCUCCACAGCUGUCAUAAUAAUAGUUCAUUAAAUAAAAUGGUGUAUUUAAAAAAAGACUUGAACAUUUCAUAAGCAACUCUUGGAGAGAUACUGCAAAUUAAUUAAGUGACCAUAAGGGCACGAUGACAAUCUGAGGUUUGAAAUUCAAGAGAAUGGUGACUCCGAGUCUGUUGGCAAGGUUAUUACCUAUUUUUCUGUUUCUGAGAAAUUUAUCUCCUAGUGCUUAGAUCAUAGAUUAAAAUAAUGCCUGAGCCUGUGAAAGUUCCCCCAGGAUUUAUUGUCUCUGUGUGUGUGUGUGUGUGUGUGUGUGUGUGUGUGUGUUGUGUGCACACACAUCUGCCCACUGCAGCACUCAGCAUGGAACUUGGCUUGUGGGGUAUUCUCAACUGAUGUAUUUAUAAAACAUGUGUAUAACAUUUAUUAUAUGCCAAUCCUUGCUCAGGUAAAAAUGUAGCUAAUUUAAUCUCCUGAUAACCUAUCAGAUCGACACUUUUACCAUCCUAUUUUACAGAUGAGAAAACUGAGGCACGGAGGGGUUAGUAAUUUGCCUGUGGUCACAAAGCUAGGAAGUGACAGAAUUAGAAUGCAAGUCCUAAGCUUUAGUUUAGGUAUCCGUGCUAGGCUCCUGUGCUACGAUGCCUCUCUCAAGAAAUCUUUCUCGAAAUGAAAUUAACAGCUUUGUCUGUGAAGAGUUUAUAAAGCAAGUUCACAUGUCAUUUCAUUUAAUCUUCAAAGUAUUCAGUAAGGAAGGUAAAGCUAUUCCCAUUUUCAGAUGGGGAAAACUGGUGCUCAGAGAGUGGGGUGAUUUUUUUCAAAUCUCCUUCCCUAGUAAAUUAUACAGCAAAGGUUAGAACAUGGACACCCCUGUCUUCAGCUCUGGCUCUCUUUCUGCCAUAGCUGCAGUGGGGUAGUAACUUCGAUAGGACUAAGAAUCCACUGCGGUCUGCCCCUUUUAUUUUUAGCCCCUCUACUGGUCUUUAUUUCUCCUGGAGAUCAGCAGUUGAUACUCAAACGCAAGGAGUAGGGAGGGAUUUUGGCAUCAAGAAUGAGUCCUCCAAACGGCUUUCCUGAAGUUCCUCCUGGUAUAUCACCCACAGUUCUUCUCACACCUCUGUUCUAUGAACAACUAGUAAUCACUAUGGUGGGAAUUAAUUUGGGAGUCAAAGUUCAAGGAAAAAAUUCUCAGGUAAUGCGCCGUUUGCUGGGCACCUAUUUAGUAGGUGAGUCUCAGGGCUUAAGGCUGCAGGUCUUCACAGUAGCCUCUCUGUUUUUCCUCUAGCACUCUUGGAGUCUCAGGGAGAAAACUGUUUUCUGGUUUGAGUCUUAUAUCCUCCCAUUUUGGCUACUGAUAGAAACCGUUACCAAUUUGGGCUGAGUUCUCUACUUCUUUCACAACAGGAGUCUUGCUUUCAAUUCAAGUUGUCAAUCAUUUUUCAAAAACCCACUCUUUAUUUAUACAUCUGUUUAUUUAUAUCCUAUCUUGUUCUACAGAAAUUAAGGGGAGCAGAGAAUAGUAAAACUACAAGUAUAAAGUAGAAAAUAAAGAUUAGAGAGGAUUGAAAUUAGAGUAGGGCAAGGCCUGAGAGAAAAAAAAAAGAGAUUUGAUUUCUGUGUUCUUAGCCAGAAAAAAUAAAACAAACAACAAAAACAAAA